GUCAUUUCCUCCUUGCGCUCGCUCGCUGCCUGAGCGUCUCCAGCCGGGAGAGUAGGCGGAGCAGGGCGGUGCGGGGUGGCGUAGAGCUGGAGGGCGAUGGUGGCGGAGCUGCUGGGGGCGGAGGCAACGUAGCCCCCUCGGAAAAGGAGCCCGGCGGCGCCUGAGCCCAGCCGAGGAUGGAGAACCGGCCUGGGUCCUUCCAGUACGUCCCUGUGCAGCUGCAAGGGGGGGCACCCUGGGGCUUCACCCUUAAGGGGGGUCUGGAACACUGUGAGCCGCUCACAGUGUCUAAGAUUGAAGAUGGAGGCAAGGCAGCUUUGUCCCAGAAGAUGAGGACUGGUGAUGAGCUGGUGAAUAUCAAUGGCACUCCAUUAUAUGGCUCCCGCCAAGAGGCCCUCAUUCUCAUCAAAGGCUCCUUCCGGAUUCUCAAGCUGAUUGUCAGGAGGAGGAACGCCCCUGUCAGUAGGCCGCACUCAUGGCAUGUGGCCAAGCUGCUGGAGGGAUGCCCUGAAGCAGCCACCACCAUGCAUUUCCCUUCUGAAGCCUUCAGCUUGUCCUGGCAUUCUGGCUGCAACACAAGUGACGUGUGUGUGCAGUGGUGUCCACUCUCCCGGCAUUGCAGCACCGAGAAAAGCAGCUCCAUUGGCAGCAUGGAGAGCCUGGAGCAACCAGGCCAAGCCACCUAUGAGAGCCAUCUGUUGCCUAUUGACCAGAACAUGUACCCUAACCAGCGUGACUCAGCCUACAGCUCCUUCUCGGCCAGCUCAAAUGCUUCUGACUGUGCCCUUUCCCUCAGGCCAGAGGAGCCAGCCUCUACAGACUGCAUCAUGCAAGGCCCAGGGCCAACUAAGGCCCCCAGUGGCCGGCCUAAUGUGGCUGAGACCUCAGGAGGUAGUCGGCGCACCAAUGGGGGCCACCUGACCCCCAGCUCUCAGAUGUCAUCCCGUCCACAGGAGGGAUACCAGUCAGGGCCCGCCAAAGCAGUCAGGGGCCCACCACAACCUCCAGUGAGGCGGGACAGCCUUCAGGCCUCCAGAGCCCAACUCCUCAAUGGAGAGCAGCGCAGGGCAUCUGAGCCUGUGGUCCCCUUGCCACAGAAGGAGAAACUGAGCUUAGAGCCUGUGCUACCCGCAAGGAACCCUAAUAGGUUCUGUUGCCUCAGUGGGCAUGACCAAGUGACAAGUGAGGGCCAUCAGAACUGUGAGUUCAGUCAGCCUCCUGAAUCCAGCCAACAGGGCUCUGAGCAUCUACUGAUGCAGGCCUCAACCAAAGCUGUUGGAUCCCCAAAAGCCUGUGACAGAGCUUCCAGCGUGGAUUCCAACCCACUCAAUGAGGCUUCUGCAGAGCUAGCUAAGGCUUCUUUUGGCAGACCUCCACAUCUCAUAGGACCCACAGGGCAUCGCCAUAGUGCCCCUGAACAGCUGCUGGCAUCCCACCUGCAGCAUGUGCACCUUGAUACCAGGGGCAGCAAAGGGAUGGAGCUCCCACCCGUACAGGAUGGGCACCAGUGGACUCUGUCCCCUUUGCACAGCAGCCACAAAGGGAAGAAAAGUCCAUGCCCCCCUACAGGAGGAACCCAUGACCAGUCCAGCAAAGAAAGAAAGACCAGACAAGUGGAUGACAGGUCUUUAGUUUUGGGACACCAGAGCCAAAGCAGUCCCCCACAUGGAGAGGCUGAUGGACACCCCUCAGAAAAAGGUUUCCUGGACCCAAACAGAACAAGCAGAGCAGCCAGUGAAUUGGCCAACCAGCAACCCUCUGCCUCUGGCUCCCUUGUUCAACAAGCCACGGACUGUUCUUCAACCACUAAAGCAGCUAGUGGCACAGAGGCAGGUGAAGAAGGGGACAGCGAGCCCAAGGAGUGCAGCCGGAUGGGUGGUAGGCGAAGUGGAGGGACCCGGGGCCGCUCGAUCCAAAACCGGCGGAAGAGUGAGCGUUUUGCUACCAAUCUGCGUAAUGAAAUUCAGAGGAGGAAGGCCCAGCUCCAGAAAAGCAAGGGUCCCUUGUCACAGCUGUGUGACACUAAGGAGCCAGUGGAAGAGACCCAGGAGCCCCCAGAAAGUCCUCCACUCACUGCCUCUAACACAUCUCUUCUAUCUUCAUGUAAAAAACCUCCCAGCCCCAGAGACAAGCUCUUCAACAAAAGCAUGAUGCUCAGAGCUAGGUCUUCCGAGUGCCUCAGCCAAGCCCCUGAGAGCCAUGAAUCUAGGACAGGCUUAGAGGGACGAAUAAGCCCUGGCCAGAGGCCUGGCCAGUCCUCUUUGGGCCUGAACACCUGGUGGAAAGCACCUGACCCAUCCUCCUCAGACCCUGAGAAAGCACAUGCUCACUGUGGAGUCCGUGGAGGUCAUUGGAGAUGGUCUCCAGAGCAUAAUUCACAGCCACUUGUGGCAGCAGCCAUGGAAGGCCCUUCCAACCCAGGUGACAACAAGGAAUUGAAGGCUUCUACUGCUCAAGCUGGGGAGGAUGCCAUCCUCUUGCCUUUUGCAGACAGAAGAAAGUUCUUUGAAGAGAGUAGCAAAUCCUUAUCUACAUCUCAUUUGCCAGGUUUAACCACUCAUAGCAACAAGACUUUUACCCAGAGACCAAAACCUAUAGACCAAAACUUCCAGCCAAUGAGCUCCAGCUGUAGGGAAUUGAGGCGCCAUCCCAUGGACCAAUCAUAUCAUUCCGCAGACCAACCAUAUCAUGCCACAGACCAAUCAUAUCAUUCCAUGUCACCCCUUCAGUCAGAAACUCCCACUUACUCAGAAUGUUUUGCAAGCAAAGGUCUAGAAAAUUCCAUGUGUUGUAAGCCACUACACUGUGGUGAUUUUGAUUACCACAGGACCUGCUCUUACUCCUGCAGUGUUCAAGGAGCUCUAGUCCAUGAUCCUUGCAUUUAUUGUUCUGGGGAAAUCUGCCCUGCCUUGCUAAAGAGAAAUAUGAUGCCAAAUUGCUACAACUGCCGGUGCCACCACCACCAAUGCAUUCGGUGUUCAGUUUGCUAUCAUAAUCCUCAGCACAGUGCCCUCGAGGACAGCAGCUUGGCACCUGGCAACACUUGGAAACCCAGGAAGCUGACAGUGCAGGAAUUUCCUGGGGACAAAUGGAAUCCAAUAACAGGAAACAGGAAGACCAGCCAGUCAGGGAGUGAGGCGCUAAAGCCUUCAUGGACGCCCGAGGAUGAAUGUAGCACAAGUACCUUUUGCUGUACCCCAGGAGUCCCUGCUUCCCUGCGAUUAUCUCUCAGAGACAGACAAGGCAGGGAAAUGGCUCAUUCCAAGACUAGCUUUUCAUGGGCAACCCCUUUCCAUCCUUGCCUUGAGAACCCAGCACUGGACUUGUCAAGCUACCGAGCAAUUUCUUCUCUUGACCUCCUUGGAGACUUCAAACAUGCUUUGAAAAAAUCAGAGGAAACUUCAGUUUAUGAGGAGGGGAGCUCCCUUGCCUCCAUGCCCCACCCACUGCGCAGCCGUGCCUUCUCAGAGAGUCACAUCAGCUUGGCGCCCCAAAGCACCCGGGCCUGGGGGCAGCAUAGGAGGGAGCUCUUUAGCAAAGGUGAUGAGACCCAGUCGGAUCUUCUCGGAGCCAGGAAGAAGGCCUUUCCUCCUCCUCGCCCUCCUCCUCCCAACUGGGAGAAGUACAGGCUCUUUCGUGCAGCCCAGCAGCAGAAGCAGCAACAGCAGCAGCAGAAGCAACAGGAGGAGGAGGAGGAGGAGGAAGAAGAAGAAGAAGAGGAAGAGGAAGAGGAGGAGGAGGAGGCAGAGGAGGAGGAAGAGGAGCUGCCACCCCAGUAUUUCAGUUCAGAAACCUCUGGUUCCUGUGCUCUCAAUCCUGAGGAGGUCCUAGAGCAGCCACAACCCCUCAGCUUUGGCCACCUGGAGGGCUCGAGACAGGGUUCACAAAGUGUCCCAGCAGAGCAAGAAUCCUUUGCACUCCAUUCCAGUGAUUUCUUGCCUCCAAUAAGGGGUCACUUGGGAUCUCAACCUGAGCAGGCUCAGCCCCCUUGCUACUAUGGCAUUGGUGGGCUUUGGAGGACAUCGGGACAGGAAGCCACUGAAUCCGCCAAACAAGAGUUUCAGCACUUUUCGCCUCCUUCAGGGGCCCCAGGAAUCCCUACCUCUUACUCAGCUUAUUACAAUAUUUCUGUGGCCAAGGCAGAGCUGCUGAACAAACUGAAAGACCAACCUGAGAUGGCAGAGAUUGGCCUAGGAGAGGAGGAAGUUGACCAUGAACUGGCUCAAAAAAAGAUACAGCUUAUCGAAAGCAUCAGCAGAAAACUUUCUGUCUUGCGGGAGGCCCAGCGAGGGCUGCUAGAGGACAUCAAUGCCAAUUCUGCCCUUGGGGAGGAGGUGGAGGCCAACUUAAAAGCCGUCUGCAAAUCCAAUGAAUUUGAAAAGUACCACUUGUUUGUUGGGGACCUGGACAAAGUGGUCAACCUGUUGCUGUCACUCUCUGGACGACUGGCCCGGGUGGAGAAUGCUCUGAACAGCAUCGAUUCAGAGGCCAACCAGGAGAAGUUGGUACUGAUAGAGAAGAAGCAGCAGCUGACGGGGCAGUUGGCAGAUGCCAAGGAGCUGAAGGAGCACGUGGACCGCCGGGAGAAGUUGGUGUUUGGCAUGGUCUCCCGCUACCUGCCUCAGGACCAGCUCCAAGAUUACCAGCACUUUGUCAAGAUGAAAUCUGCUCUCAUCAUUGAACAGCGAGAGCUGGAGGAGAAGAUCAAGCUCGGGGAAGAGCAACUCAAAUGUCUCAGGGAGAGUCUACUCCUGGGGCCCAGCAAUUUCUAAUUCUACCAGCACUCUGCCACAGCAUCCCUGCCCAGCCAUGUGGGAAGUGCUUUCAAUCUUCUUUGUUAGCAGUUUCUCAGCAAGUAGAUAGCAAUUAGCAGUUUGUUCCAGCCCUCUACCCUGGAUGUCUCUCACUACCCCUUCCCUAGCAGUGGUCCUAACCAGCUAGGAGACCCUGGGGAAGCCACAAGCUUCUACCCAAGGGAGCUGCAGCAAGGUGUGAUCUUAGAACCACACUCUCCUUCCCACAGUUGCCAAGGGCAAGUACUUGCUGCACAGAGAACCAAGGAAGUGCCUUCAUUCUGCUUUGUACUAGGACACCAAAGACAUCAAGUACUCAUCACCCACCCAUAUCAUCAACAGCCUCUAAAGGCUCAGAGGGAAUCUGCCUUGCAGCUCUACUCUGCCCCAGGGCUUGUGGCCAGCCAUUUCUCACAGAGAGCUGGCUGCCUUGAGGGCAUUCACCUGGCACCAGUUUCAGGGCCUCACCCAAGCUUUGCAGGGGAAAGCACAGAGGGAGGAAUUACACUGAAAAAAAUGCAAGCAAAGGUUGAGUACCCCCAGGUGCCCCUUAGGAAGGAACCAGGUUUAAAUAGGCUCUACCCUUACCUUUCCCAGCAGCAAGUUCAGGGGAAGAGGCCUACUCUUAGCCCUGGCUAGUGUGACCCUCUUCCUGUCCUAAGACUUUGGUCCUACCACCUCUUGUUUCAUCUUUCCUUUACAUUGCUGGGGGUUACCGCAGGUGCCUACCCCAGGGCUUCACCAUAUGGGCCAUUAAUAGCUCUACUAAAACUGACUUCUAGAUGUAGGUUUCAUUAUUGGGGGAGGGGGUUCUUAUUGUUAUAUUUUAAAUGGCCUUUUGAUUUUAUUUAUUUUUAUGUUUUGAUUAUUUUUUUCUUUUUUAACUAAUAAGGCGAGAAGAGGGAAGUUGGAGAGGGAAAAGUUAGCCCAGAAGGAAAGCAUUUUCUGCAGAUCAGCCUGAAUCCACCGUGGCUAGGUAAGCAAGUGCCAAGGCGUUGAAUUGUUCCCACCAUAGCUACCGAUGUCUAGGAAGGAGUUUUCCCCUUGAACUCAGAGCCUCCCUACUGUGGCCUGGCCUUGUGCUUCCCUUAAAGUCUAAGUGACUUGAGUUUAGCAUUCCCCAGCAGGGUUUAAGUUUUUCUUACUGAUUUCUUUUUGAAACCAAAGAAAUCUCCUGAAAUGGAGAAAGGUUCAGUCAUUUCUCUACCAUCUCCAAGCUAUGGGAUCAGUAGAGGUGAGCUCAGAAGGAACUCCUCUAACCAUUGCUUUCUCAGCCUGUGGCCUGGCUCAAGGGAACCAAAACUCAAGGUAGCUGGGAGCUCCAGCCAGAGCCAGCUCCCCAGAGCAAUUGAAGACCCAGCCAGGAUCUUAGGCAUACAAACAACUAAAACUGCUGCUGUUGCCAAGGCCCUGACACCAGUAGCUAGUUUCUAUGCUGGAAAAGCAGCCCUCAGGUGGACGAUGGCAAGAAGGGGGUUAUGGCCAAAUGCUGCCCUGUUAUCCAGCUUAGCUCCCUGUUCCUCACUAACUGGGGCCAAUCCUUGGUAUCACACAACCCAGCCAAGGCCUGGCAUCUCUUCUAGUUACUGCUGAGUUCCUCAGGGUCCUUGAAGGUCAACUGUAGCAGCAGGGAUGUCUCAUUCAACCAAAGAAUUUGCCAAGGAACUUUUGCUGCUGUUACAAAUACUUGUCACUAGCUUCCAUUUCCUCUUCAUUGUAUUUGAAAACAAUGGGAGAAUCUUGGCCAGCAGGGUGUCCUGGGGUAGGGGGUGGGGUAAGCCUUUCUGUGGAGCUCUGGGUUUGCUCUUAGUACUGCUGCCAGAAACACUGUUAGAAUGGCAACCCUGCCAUUCUCCCCUCCAGUGGAAGAUUCUACUUUAUUCAGGAAGGCUGGUGGCUUGCAGGGGCUAGGCUUACACAAGCCAGCCAAGAUUGAGAAGGUAGGGGAGUGCUUUCAAUGGAGGCCAUAGUUGUCAUCUUUUCUUCUGAGCAGGCUCUAGGACAAACAAUGAGCAAAUUGAGAUGUCCUGUAUUGGGAGGAUGAGGCUGAUAUGUUUCAUCAUUCUCAGAAUUUGUGGGCUAGAGCACCUUUUUGGGAAUAUGGGCCUAGGGAAAAGAACGGUCACUUACCUGGACACUAUGGCCAUAGUCUUGAGUUUUUCUAGUCAGCAUGUGAUUGGUUGUACCUUAAGUUUAUGACACCAAAAAUACUAUUAACUCUGUUAUUUUUGUUCUUAAUCCCAUCUCAAAUUAGUUUCUAGAGUUAGAAUCAGAACACAAGGAUGCUCAUUUUCACAUGGAGGGAAAGUUGCCAAAGCAUUUAAAAAAUAACCCCAAAAGUAUAUCUAGCAGUGAAGCUUGGUAGAUAAAGGUGAACUGCUAAACAGACACUGGCGUGCCACACUCCUGCCAGGGCAGUCUCAUUGUGUGUGACGGUGCUGCAACACUGCCAGUAUUACUUGAGAUGCAGUCUCUCUCCCCUGUUCUCAGUUCCUGGGCUCAGCCCUCCUCCAAGGCCUGCCAGUGAGUAGCAGUUUGGAAGGCAGGCCAAGGGAGAUCCCCAAAGACAGUUAUCAGUCUUAACUUCUGCUGUCUCCCGUCAAAUACUUAUACAGGCCCCCAUGGGUAAUAGGCAAGCAUGAUGGCUGAUAGAGAAGUCAGUGCAUGAGUUACUAUCACAUGUCCCCCCAACCCCUCCUGCCACCUCCCAGGGCUCUGGAUAAUUGAAUCUUCCUGAGUCCCACAGCUGGAGACUCAACCAGGAUAUAGCUGUAAAUGCCCAAGUAGAAUCUGACAGAAUAAGACAGAGACACUGAAAAUAAAGCCCUAGAAAGGAAGAAAUUGGAAGCAAAGAAAAGGAGAGGUGAAAAGAUAAAAAGCCUCCUUCAAGGUUAGGUUCAGGUUCUGUUUUCCAUUUAACCUCAUGUGCCAUAAAGCUGCCCAGGCACACCAGAGCCACAUCCUGAACCCGACCCUCCCUGACAGUGCUGCUCUGCCAGUAGCAAGCCCCAGAUGGAGGAAGCUGGGCCCAUUUCUGGCCACUUCCACCCAUUUGGAGCUUUGCCAGAGGAGUCGUCUAUGCCAAUAAUAUUUCUGCAACAGCAUAUUAUAUUAUUUGAAGAUUAGUAGAUCUUUUUGGGGGGGUGGGGCAGGGGACAGUUUCUAUAGAUGAAGAACCAGUGUUGGUUGUACAGCUGUUGGGGGUCAUCUAUCCCAUGUGAAGCUAUUCUUUUUCCAAAUCUUGUUGUUUCUGCAUUUGUGUCCUCCACCACUCCCUUCUUGGCUGACAUAGAUAUGCCUGCCAGAUUGUCAUCAAGGGUCAUAUUUCAAUAAAAGGUGCUAAGGACAAAAAAAAAUCUCAUGUGUUUUAACUCAGGUGAUGGAAGUCUAAAGAUUCUGCUGAAAAGUACUGGAAAGGAAUUUGGUCACCUAUCCAUAGUCCUUCACAGAUAAACAUAUGACCAGACCCUUACCCACAUCCCUAAACCCUUACCCUGGCCUCUGAGGGAUGGUAUUGAUGCUAUACCAUUCAUCAUCCCCAGUUAAAUAGCAGGAUCUGCCAUAGCCUUUUUAGGGGAACAGCUUUUAGACAUCUAUUUCAAGACCAUCCUGAGUAGGGGGUACAGAGUUUAAGCCAUUGGUUAUUUCUGUUGUUAUCACAGUAUUGAAGCAUGGUAUUUUUCUACUCAGAAGGAUCUCAGGAUCACAGCCCUGCCCUUUAGCUCACUGAUAUAUUUCUUCCUCUCUGGUUACUCAGUGGCAACAUCACAUCCAGUCUAACCCCAUGUUUAGAAUGCAGAAAAAGUCAACAAUAGGUGUAAUCUCAGGUAUAGACCUAAGCAGUAUACAGAGUCUAGUUCUGGAGUCUAGCCUGAUCGAAGGUAAGCCAUUCUUUCUAGACUUCUUCCAAUCUUGAAUUCUGUCUAGUAUUUUCAUCUUACUUCUAGCUGAUAGUCCAAUCUCACACCUUCAUGCUCAGCUCCCUGGAAAGCAAGGGCCUUGGUGAUCUGCUCUCCAAGGCAACCUCAAAGAUUAGACUCAAAUGUAUUCCAGGAAGCAACUCUGACAUUGAAAAGCUUUCUUUUUUCGUGAUCCAUAUUCUGUUCACAUUCCAACUAUCCUCCUUCUACUCAAGAUAUCCAUUGUGGUAGAGUAGAAAGAGUCCAGCUUUGGCAUUAGAAUGAACUGUGUUCAAAUCCUGGUUCUGCCACUUAUUCAAUGAACCUGGGCUACUAGCUCAACUUCUGAGGUCAUUUUCUUAUCUGUAAAAUGGGAACAGUAUUAUCUUGCUUGCAGUUAUUGUAACUUGAAAAUAAUAAAUAAAAGCCACUAACAAUCCAAGAAGUUAUUAGGCAGAAUCCCAGGCCCACCCCAAACCCAGUGAUAGCAGUCUGAAUUUUAACUAGAUUUCCAGGAGAUUCAUGAACAUAUUACAGCAUGGGAAGUACUGACUUGUUGAAAACAUAUUCAGUACAUGGUAACCAUUAUUAUAGUCCUGAUCUACUCAAUUCAUUUUUUCCUUAUCCCAGGCAUAUUCUUGCUCUUCUCGUGUUGCUCACAACUACCUGCCUGGAUGAAUUUAGGAAAGUUGCAGGAUACAAGGUUAAAACACAAGAUCAAAUGAACAAUCCGAAAAUGUUAUUAAGAAAACAGUUCCGGCCGGGCAUGGUGGCUCACGCCUGAAAUCCCAGCACUUUGGGAGGCCGAGGCAGGUGGAUCACGAGGUCAGGAGAUCAAGACCAUCCUGGCUAACACGGUGAAACCCUAUCUCUACUAAAAAUACAAAAAAUUAGCCAGGUGUGGUGGCACGCACCAGUAGUCCCAGCUACUCGGGAGGCUGAGGCAGGAGAAUUGCUUGAACCUGGAAGGCAGAGAUUGCAGUGAGCUGAGACCACACCACUGCACUCCAUCCUGGGCAACAGAGUGAGACUUUGUCUCAAAAAGAAAGAAAGAAAGAAAGAAAGAAAGAAAGAAAGAAAAGAAAGAAAGAAAGAAAGAAAGAAAACAGUUCCAUUUACAAUAGCAUCAAAAAGAAAAAAGUACUUAGGAAUAAUUUAACAAAAGAAGUGCGAAACUUUUACACUGAAAACUAUAAAACAUUGUUGAAAGAGAUUAGAGAAGAUCAAAAUAAAUGGAAAGACACUCCAUGUUCAUGGAUUGGAAGACUUAGUAUUGUUAAGAUGAAAUGUGCCCCAAAUUGAUCUACAGAUUCAAUCCAGUGCUUAUCAGAAUUCCAGUGGCUUCCUUGUGUAAGUUUACAAGCUGAUUCUAAAAUUCAUAUGGAAUUACAAGGGACCUGGAACAGUCAAAACAAUCUUUAAAAAGAACAGUUGGAGGGCUCAUACAUCCCAACUUCAAAACUUACUGCAAAACUACAGUAAUCAAGACAGUGUGGUACAGACACAAGGGUAGGUGUAUAAAUAAAUGGAAUUAAAUUGAGAGUCCAGAAAUAAAUCCUCAUGUAUAUGGUUAGUUAAUUUCAACAAGGGUCCCAAGAGAAAUUGAGGAGAGAAUAGUUUUUUAACAAAUGAUGCUGAGACAACUGGGUAUCUACAUGGGAAAAAAUGAAGUUUUCCUUAAAUCACAUGCAAGAAUCAACUCAAAAUGGAUUAUAGAAUGUAAGAGUCAAAAUUAUAAAAUUCUUAGAAGAAAACAUUGUAAUAAGUCUUCCUAAUGUUAAGACGAUUUGCACAAGUGAUACAAGAAAUAGAAAUAAAUUGGAGUAAAUCAAAAUUAAAAACUUUUGUGCUAAAAAUAUACCAUAUAAAAAAGUGAAAAGACAAGCAACAUAAUAUUAGGAGAAAAUAUUUGCAUAUCAGAUACUUCAAAAUAUGAAAAGGACUCUUACAACUCAAUGAUAAAAAUAACCAAUUAAAAAUGGGUUAACAGAUUGUAAUAGACAUUUCUUCAAAGAAAAUAUGUGUUUUAGUAUGCUUGGGUUGCUAUAACAUACUACCAUAGACUGAUUGUCUUAAAUAACAUUUAUUUCUCACAGUCCUGGAGACUGGGAAAUCUGAGAGCAAGAUGCCAGCAGAUUCAAUGCCUUGUGAGGGCCCACUUUAUGGUUUGCAGAUGGCUACCUUGUGGCUGUGUCCUCAGCAAAGACAGAAAGGGAUCUGGUCUCGGCCAGGCGCGGUGGCUCACGCCUGUAAUCCCAGCACUUUGGGAGGCCGUGGCGGGCGGAUCAGGAGGUCAGGAGAUCGCAACCAUCCUGGCUAACACGGUGAAACCCCAUCUCUACUAAAAAAAAUACAAAAAAAUUAGCAGGGCAUGGUGGCAGGUGCCUGUAGUCCCAGCUAGUCGGGAGGCUGAGGCAGGAGAAUGGCGUGAACCCAGGAGGCGGAGCUUGCAGUGAGCAGAGAUUGAGCCACUGCACUCCAGCCUGGGUGACUGAGCGAGAUUCUGUCUCAAAAAAAAGAAAGGGAUCUGGUCUCUUCCCCUUCUUAUAAGGGCAUUAUAAUUUCAUUAUGAAUGCCUACUCUUGUGACUUCAUCUAAACCAAUUUACCUCUCAAAGGCCCCACCUCCAUAUGCCAUCACAUUGGGGAUUAGGGCUUCAGCAUGUGAGUUUGGAGAGGACACAAACAUUCAGCUUAUAGCAAUAUGCAACUGGCUAGCAAGCACAGGGAAAGAUGCUCAAGCACUACUAUUCAUUAGGGAAAUGCAAAUCAAGACCACAAUGAGAUACCACUUCAUACCCACUAGAAUAGCUAUAUCAAAAAGCCAAACAAUAACAAGUGUUGGUGAGGAAAUGAAGAAAUUGGAACACUCAUACAUUGCUGAUGGGGAUGUAAAUUGAUGCAACCUCAUUGAAAAACAGCUUGGCAGUUUCUCCAAAUGUUAAACAUAGAAUUUCCACAUGACUUAGCAAUUCCAUCCCUAGGUAUAUACCCAAGAGAAUUGGAAACAGGUGUUCAAACAAAAGCGUGAACAUGAAUGUUUAAAGUGGCAUUACUCAUAAUAGCCAAAAAGUGGAAAUGACCCAAAUGUCCAUCCACUGAGGAAUGGAUAAACAAACUUUGAUAUAUGCAUACAGUAGGGUAUUAUUUAGCCAUAAAAAUGGAUAAAAUACUGAUACAUGUAACAUUGAUGAACCUUGAAAAUAUGCUAAGUGAAAGGAGCCAAUCACAAAAGACCACAUAUUGUAUGAUUUAAUUUAUAUGAAAUGUCCCAAACAGGCAAAUCUAUAAAGGUAGAAAGCAGAUUAGUGGUUGUCAAGGCUGGGGGCUCAGGGGCAAUAGGCAUGGGGUUUCUUUUGGGGAUGAUGAAAAUAUUAUAAAAUUAGAUUGUCAUCCUGGUUGUCCAACUCUGAAUGUACUGGAAACCAUUGAAGUAUACAUUUUAAAUGGGUGUGCUAAAUGGUAUAUGAAUUAUUUCUCAAUAAGUGUGUUUUUUUAAAAAAGCUAUUGAUUAUUUCCAUCAGUCUCAUUCCUCUUGACAAAAAUCUGAGUUGAUGGUGAGCAUGUACUUCAUUCCUGACUCCAAAGGGUACAAUAUUUACAAUAUUUGAAUUUGGGAGUGACUUUACUAUUACAACCUUCCCCUUGAAGACCUGGAAGACCCAGCAACAUAAGGACAAACAGUAGUCUCAGCCUUGUACUAAGACUUCAGCAAAAAUAAGAGAGAUGGGAGGGACUACUAUUGGGAAGGAGGGGCAAUAUUUCUAGGCAAAUAUUGUGGUAGAAUGGAUAAGAGCUUCGGCUCAUUGGGCAAAUAAACCAAGUUUUAAAUCCUGAUUCUACCAAUUUACUGUGUCACCUUAAUAAGUUACUUGACUCCUCUCAACCUUAAUACCUUCAUCUACAGAAGGGGGCUAAUAAAAGCCCCACCUCAAAGUGUUACUAUGUUGAUUAAAUGAGAUAAUUCACAUGAAGCACUUAAAAUAAUGUCUGCCAUGUAGUAAGUAUUUGAUAAAUGUUAGCUGCUAGAUUUAUUUUUAUUGAGGUGAGAUUGAAGUAGAACAAUAUAAGGAAAAGUAAAGCAUCUUCAGCUUUGGAGUCAGACAGCUCUGUUAAUGUGACCUUGGAAGUCACUUUAUUUAUUGAGCCUUAGCAAAUAAUGAGGAUAGUAAUCCUUCUCUUACAGAGGCAGUUCCAAGCCUGGACACUGGAACCCACACCACGUAGGUUUUCAUACUGGCUCCACCACUUACACAUUGUGUAACCUUGAGCAUGUUUAACUUCCCUGUACCUGGAUGUCCUCUUCUGUCAAAUGGUGGAAACAAAAAUACAUCCUUGUGUUGUGAGGAAUUAUUGAGUUAAUCCAUGCAAAGUACUUAGGACAAUAAGUACCCAAUGAAUGUUAACUUUUAUUAUAAAGCUAAAGUAGGAAUCAAAUGAGGUCUCUGGUAGAGCUGUUCAUAUGGUAGGUUCUCCGUAGAUGAUGGUUCCUUUCCUUACCUACCCUGCUGUGUGCACCAGGUCAAGAUUUUUUGGACCUGCAGAUAAAAUGUUUCAGCCUUAGGAGUUCCCCACUGUAAGUAAAAUUUUCUGGCAAGCUCAAUACUACCAUCUGAUGAGAACAAUGUAGUCUGUUAGCUGCCUGCAAGAUGACUAGUCUAUACUCCCAAGAAAACACCCCCUUCAGAACAAUAGAGAAGGAACUGUUUUGCAUGUGGACCACUUAAGGUCCAAUUUGAGGCUGGUUUGGGGAAAACAUCCACUCCUCCUCAAACCUAUCUUUAGACUUAAAGUCAACUUAAAUGUCAUUGAGUUUCCCACCCUGGGUUAAGCACUUUCACUUAUCUUUGCUUACACUAUUUUUCUAUCUAAACAUACAUUUUUAAAGCAGAAAUCCUCAUUUAAUCUUUAAAACAGAUCUGUGAUUUUGAAACACUAUUUAAUCAAAAUUCAGAAUUGUGGUAGCAUUUUUGCUGUUUGUAAGUUAAACAAAAUAGAUUGUAAGUGUGCAAUGCCAUUCAUUCAUUCAACUAAUGUGCCAAUAAUUUGUUUUGUGCUUCAGGGAUUCAGAAGUGGACAAGAUAGACAAAGUCCCCACUCUCGUGGGGCUUUUAUCCUAAUGAAAGAGAUAGAUAAGUAUAAAUAUACAAUUACAUAAUACUUUAUAUACAGAAAUAUACACACAAUCACUUUUUACCCUGGUAUGGCAAUGCGAAACAUUCUUCCUUGAUUUCUUCAGCUAUGUGCAAUAGGCUAAACUCAUGAAUCUCUUUGCUACUGCAGUAACUAAAAUAUUUUUUGCAUUAAUUUUCACCAGAGAAUAAUGUUUCAGUGAACAUGAGAGUGCAGAUAUCUCUUCGAGAUACUGAUUUCAUUUCCUUUGGGUAUUUACCCAGAAGAAGAAUCUCUGCAUCAUAUGGUCAUCGUAUUCUUAAUAUUUUGAGGAAUAUACACUAUUUUCCAAAAUGGGGUACUAAUUUACAUUCCCACCAACAAUGUACCAGGGUUUCCUUUCCUCCAUACCCUCAUCAACAUUUGUUAUCCCUUGCCUUUUUGAUAAAAGCCUGCUAUUUAUGACAAAAUGGAUGAACCCGGAGGGUAUUAUGCUAAGUGAAACAAACCAGACACAGAAAGAAAAAUACUGCGUAAUCUCAUAUGUGGAAGCUAAAAAAGUCAAACACACAGGGGGAUGGAGGUGGAAGAAAUGAGGAUGUUGGUCAAAGCUACAAAGUUGCAGCUACAUAAGAUGUAUAAAUCUAGAGAUCUCAUGUACAGCAUAAGUUCUAUAGUUAAUAAUGCUGUAUUGAAUACUGGAAAUUUUCUAAGAGUAGAUUUCAGGUGCUCUUACUGCAAAAGAGGGUAAUUAUGUGAGGAAAUGCAUAUUUAAUUUGCAUGACUGUAGCAAUCAUUUCACUAUGUAAUGGAUGUCAAAACAUCAUUUGUACACCUUAAAUAUAUACAAUAAAAGAUUUUCACCAAA